GACUGAGUCAUAGACAGGAGAGAGACCCCCCUAGCAUCAGAGAGAGAGAGAGAGAUCAACAGAGCCAGAGAGGGACAAGUACAGAGAAACAGAUGGAACCAGAGAGAUAUAGGAAGAGACAAACAAAAACAGAGACGGAGUUGCAGAACCGGAGGAAGGGAGAGAGACAGAGACAAAGGCAUUUAUAAAGACGGGUGGAGGUGAGGAGAGAGAGGGAGAGACAGGGGCAAGCAUUUAGAGAGUGACUCCCAGAGAGGAAGACAGAGACGGACUCCCAAAGAGAUCAAGUUGCAGAGGGAGGGGGAGACAGAGUCACAGCCUGAGAGAGAAUAGAGAUUCACAGAGCCAGAGAGACAAAGACAGGGAAAGAAACAAACUCAGGGAGACAGAGGCGGAAGAAUUUAUCAGACGUAGAGGGAGAGACAGAGGGAGACUGAUUCACAGUGAGGCAGACCAAGACCCCGAGAAGAACCACGACACCAAGACCCAGAGAUGGCGACAGAUACAGAUGGAGACACACAGCAGAGGAAAUAGAGAAAUAGAAAGAAAUAGAAACAGCAUUUCUCGGAGACAGGGAAAAGAAAACAGAUCCACUGAGAGGCAGAAACAGAGACACAUCGAGAAAGCUCGCUCCAGGAAUAGAGGGAGAGGGACAGAGGUCACAAGAAAGACACACGCAGGCAGAGAGCUACACAAAUAAUGGAGAGGCCAGGGGAGGAAAUAAAGACUCAGCCGGCAUCGGAGAAAAAAGGGGGCCCUGAGGCAGAAGGUGGUCCACGAAGUCAAGAGCCACAAGUUCACCGCUCGCUUCUUCAAGCAGCCCACCUUCUGCAGCCACUGCACCGACUUCAUCUGGGGUAUCGGAAAGCAGGGCCUGCAAUGUCAAGUCUGCAGCUUUGUGGUUCAUCGACGAUGCCACGAAUUUGUGACCUUCGAGUGUCCAGGCGCUGGGAAGGGCCCCCAGACGGACGACCCCCGGAACAAACACAAGUUCCGCCUGCAUAGCUACAGCAGCCCCACCUUCUGCGACCACUGUGGCUCCCUCCUCUACGGGCUUGUGCACCAGGGCAUGAAAUGCUCCUGCUGCGAGAUGAACGUGCACCGGCGCUGUGUGCGUAGCGUGCCCUCCCUGUGCGGUGUGGACCACACCGAGCGCCGCGGGCGCCUGCAGCUGGAGAUCCGGGCUCCCACAGCAGAUGAGAUCCACGUAACUGUUGGCGAGGCCCGUAACCUAAUUCCUAUGGACCCCAAUGGUCUCUCUGAUCCCUAUGUGAAACUGAAGCUCAUCCCAGACCCUCGGAACCUGACGAAACAGAAGACCCGAACGGUGAAAGCCACGCUAAACCCUGUGUGGAAUGAGACCUUUGUGUUCAACCUGAAGCCAGGGGAUGUGGAGCGCCGGCUCAGCGUGGAGGUGUGGGACUGGGACCGGACCUCCCGCAACGACUUCAUGGGGGCCAUGUCCUUUGGCGUCUCGGAGCUGCUCAAGGCGCCCGUGGAUGGCUGGUACAAGUUACUGAACCAGGAGGAGGGCGAGUAUUACAAUGUGCCGGUGGCCGAUGCUGACAACUGCAGCCUCCUCCAGAAGUUUGAGGCUUGUAACUACCCCCUGGAAUUGUAUGAGCGGGUGCGGAUGGGCCCCUCUUCCUCUCCCAUCCCCUCCCCUUCCCCUAGUCCCACCGACCCCAAGCGCUGCUUCUUCGGGGCGAGUCCAGGACGCCUGCACAUCUCCGACUUCAGCUUCCUCAUGGUUCUAGGAAAAGGCAGUUUUGGGAAGGUGAUGCUGGCCGAGCGCAGGGGCUCUGAUGAGCUCUACGCCAUCAAGAUCUUGAAAAAGGACGUGAUCGUCCAGGACGACGAUGUGGACUGCACGCUGGUGGAGAAACGUGUGCUGGCGCUGGGGGGCCGGGGUCCUGGCGGCCGGCCCCACUUCCUCACCCAGCUCCACUCCACCUUCCAGACCCCGGACCGCCUGUAUUUCGUGAUGGAGUACGUCACCGGGGGAGACUUGAUGUACCACAUUCAACAGCUGGGCAAGUUUAAGGAGCCCCAUGCAGCGUUCUACGCGGCAGAAAUCGCUAUCGGCCUCUUCUUCCUUCACAAUCAGGGCAUCAUCUACAGGGACCUGAAGCUGGACAAUGUGAUGCUGGAUGCUGAGGGACACAUCAAGAUCACUGACUUUGGCAUGUGUAAGGAGAACGUCUUCCCCGGGACGACAACCCGCACCUUCUGCGGGACCCCGGACUACAUAGCCCCGGAGAUCAUUGCCUACCAGCCCUAUGGGAAGUCUGUCGAUUGGUGGUCCUUUGGAGUUCUGCUGUAUGAGAUGUUGGCAGGACAGCCUCCCUUCGAUGGGGAGGACGAGGAGGAGCUGUUUCAGGCCAUCAUGGAACAAACUGUCACCUACCCCAAGUCGCUUUCCCGGGAAGCCGUGGCCAUCUGCAAGGGGUUCCUGACCAAGCACCCAGGGAAGCGCCUGGGCUCAGGGCCUGAUGGGGAACCUACCAUCCGUGCACAUGGCUUUUUCCGCUGGAUUGACUGGGAGCGGCUGGAACGAUUGGAGAUCCCGCCUCCUUUCAGACCCCGCCCGUGUGGCCGCAGCGGCGAGAACUUUGACAAGUUCUUCACGCGGGCGGCGCCAGCGCUGACCCCUCCAGACCGCCUAGUCCUGGCCAGCAUCGACCAGGCCGAUUUCCAGGGCUUCACCUACGUGAACCCCGACUUCGUGCACCCGGAUGCCCGCAGCCCCACCAGCCCAGUGCCUGUGCCCGUCAUAUCCUGCACCCCAGCAUUCCAGCUCUGCCCCCGCGGGUUCUAGACGCCCCUCCCAAGCGUUCCUGGCCUUCUGAACUCCAUACAGCCUCUACAGCCGUCCCGCGUUCAAGACUUGAGCGGAGCCCGAUAUUCUCCCUGACCUUAGCGUUCUGGACUCUGCCCCAAUCGGGUCCAGAGACCACACCACUAACCAUCCCCAACUCCAUGGGGUUCGAGACUCCAUCUUGGUAGUUCUGUGCCUCCCCCCAGACCCCGCCCCUGGGGAAAUAGCCUCACGGGGUUGGCUGUUCCAGACUCAGGUUCCAGAACAGCCCUCGGCCUCCGAGGCUCCCCGCCUCCACUCUAGUUCUAGAUGAGUGGGAGGCGUGCCCCCCUCCUCCAGUACGUCCCGCUGCUGUGCUCUGGGGAUUUCUGGGAUAUAUGGAGGAUUCUUUCCCCAGAGGCUCCCAAUCAGCUUUUGUUCUAGACUUCCCCAUCCCGAAGCCAUCACUUCUCCCCGCAGCCCGCCUGCCGUGCAUGGCUCCUGUCUGGCUCGGACCCACCCCAACUCUCCCCAGUGCCUGCCACUCUCUGGGACUCUCCUCCUCCCCUCCUCUUCCCUUAGCCUCUCCCACCCGGCCACAGCUGCUGGAGAAUAAAUUUGGGAUGCUGAUGCUGAA